GGCUCCACACCUGCACCUCCCUCUCACCUGCUCCUCUACCUGCUCCACCCUCAAUCCACCAGAACCAUGGGCUGCUGUGGCUGCUCCGGAGGCUGUGGCUCCGGCUGUGGAGGCCGUGGCUCCGGCUGUGGGGGCUGUGGCUCCGGCUGUGGAGGCUGUGGCUCUGGCUGUGGGGGCUGUGGCUCCGGCUGUGGAGGCUGUGGGGGCUGUGGCUCCGGCUGUGCGGGCUGUGGGGGAUGUGGCUCCGGCUGCUGUGUGCCUGUCUGCUGCUGCAAGCCCAUGUGCUGCUGUGUGCCAGCUUGUUCCUGCUCCAGCUGUGGCAAAGGGGGCUGUGGCUCUUGCGGGGGCUCCAAGAGAGGCUGUGUCUCCUGUGGGGUGUCCAAGGGGGCCUGUGGCUCCUGUGGGGGGUCCAAGGGGGGCUGUGGCUCCUGUGGGGGGUCCAAGGGGGGCUGUGGCUCCUGUGGGGGGUCCAAGGGGGGCUGUGGCUCCUGUGGGGGGUCCAAGGGGGGCUGUGGUUCUUAUGGCUGCUCCCAGUCCAGCUGCUGCAAGCCCUGCUGCUGCUCCUCAGGCUGUGGGUCAUCCUGCUGCCAGUCCAGCUGCUGUAAGCCUUACUGCUGCCAGUCCAGCUGCUGUAAGCCCUACUGCUGCCAGUCCAGCUGCUGUAAGCCCUGUAGCUGCUUCUCAGGCUGUGGAUCAUCCUGCUGCCAAUCCAGCUGCUACAAGCCCUGCUGCUGCCAGUCCAGCUGCUGUGUCCCCGUGUGCUGCCAGUGUAAGAUCUGAGGCUCUGACUGCAGACUGCAGGUGGCCUGACUGGUGAAGGGCCCGGCUGCCCAGCUUCCUUGCCCUGGGUUCUCUGGUGCUCCACUGUCUCCACUGUGUCCUCACUGGCUUCAUCCACUCCACACCAGUGCUCCCGAAACUGACUGAGGACCCCUUCUGGCUCAUUGCCUACUACUUCUCCUGAACUUCCUCUCCCUGCUCCUCACUCAUUUAAGAUCCAAAGCGGCCCACUGAGGCCCCAGAGGCAGAUCAGACCCCUUAGACCCUGACAGCUGCUCCUUCUUUCAGGAGUGUGAUCGACCCUCAAUCUCUCUGGCUGUCUGUAUAUCAAGACUGAAUCCUGACCCUCUAAAUAAACAAAGUCUCUAAGCACAAA